ACACGGGCCUUCCACGAGGGCCCCUGUGGGCAGCGUCCGGCCCCUGCCCAGGACCAGCGUUUGGUCCUGGGUGUGGAGAAAUUCAGCCUCUGAGAGCCACCCCUGUCUCACAGCUCUGGUGGCCACCAGUCGGGAAGAUGCCCCUUCCGCCACUGUGUGUGGCCCAUUGGGUUCUAGAACUUUCUACAACUACGUUUACUAGACUCAUUUCUGGCUUGGCCAUUCCCUCACCCUCUUGGCCUUUGCCUCUCUCUACGUGGCCGCCUGGCCAUGGCUUUCUGUCCUGUUCUCCUGAGAGCCGUCCACCUGCAGGCCGAGAUGAAUCAUCUCCGGCAUUCGGAUCCACUACCCAUUCAUUCCAUCACCUUCCAGGCCUUGCUCCAUGACAAGCACUGGGACCUGGGCUCUCCCUGGUGGCACUCACUGACCAGGGGAUUUCCUCCUAUGAGCAAGCCUUCCCUGGUCACGGGGGGAUACCCUACAGGGAGCAGCCAGAUCUCUUCUCCCUGGGUGCCCCUCCUUGGGGUCUGUCAGACUGUGAGGCUAGCCACCUCCCCUGAGCCCUGCUUCUCUGCUGCUUGGAAGAGACUUGCCAGGGAAGAUAGAUCUCCCCGCUGCAGCAGGGUCUGGGGGUCAGCUUGGGGCAUGGCACCGUAGAUUCCAAAGCACAGGCUUGAGCUAGGGCUGGGCAGGGAUGGUAGGAGGAUCUUUUUAAUUUUUUUUAAUUUUUAUUUUUUGAAACAGGGUCUCGCUCUGUUGCCCAGGCUGGAGUGCAGUAGCGUGAUCUUGACUCACUGCAAUUUCCGCCUCCUGGGUUCAAGCAAUUCUCCUGCCUCAGCCUUCCGAGUAGCUGGGACUAUAGGUAUGUGCCAACACGCCUGGCUAAUUUUUAUACUUUUAGUAGAGACGGGGUUUCAUCAUGUUGCCCAGGCUGGUCUUGAACUCCUGGCUUCAAGCAAUCCUCCUGCCUCAGCCUCCCAAAGUGCUGGGAGAUGUAGUCUCGCCCUGUCACCCAGGCUGGACUGCAAUGGCACAAUCUCGGCUCACUGCAACCUCUGCCUCCCGGGUUCAAACGAUUCUCCUGCCUCAGCCUCCCGAGUAGCUGGGAUUACAGGUGCCCACCACCACACCCAGCUAAUUUUUGGAUUUUUAGUAGAGAUGGGGUUUCACCAUGUUGGGCAGGCUGGUGGACAUCAUAUAUUAAUCUGAUUUAAUCCUCAUGACCCUCUUAGUGCUCAUGACAGAUCAGGAAACUGAGGCCCAGACAUCCCCAAUGAUACGUAGCCAAUAGAGCUGGGGUCAAAGCCCAGAUCUGACUCCAAAGAGGAUGGCAGGAACAGGAUGGGACCAUGGAUGGGAUCCCCAUGGUGCCAGUGGUCGCCUGCUUCUGGUGACUGUAGCAGGGGAUGCUCCUCCAUCCCUCUGGUAGCAGCUCUUAGCACAAAUUCUUCCUACAGCAACUUGCAGCUUUCCAGAAUCUCCACAACUCAAUCUACUCUGACAUGUUCCUUGAGCAUCUCUCUCUGGGCAAGGCCAGAAAGGCCAUCCCUGUUCUUAUGAUGUGGAGGCUGCCCUGAACAGUGAACCCCGGGACCUGAUAGGGGAGGCCCUGAUGGCAGAGGAGGAGGAAAGAAAAAACCUCCUGACCUCUUGCAGGGCAGUGGGUUGCUGUGAAUGUCUCCACCCAGCAGCACUUGACUCAAAAAGUGGGUCAAUGACCUUGCCCCUCCCUGGCUACUGCACAGGAAACAUGAGAGUAAAGGUGUCCCAGACCAUGACUUUUACUACCCCCGGGCCACGCCCCGGGAAUUCCUCUGAUGCCUCAGCUCUCCCAGCUCACCAGGGGCUAGAGACAGGCGCUGUUUUGGGGUUGGCCCUACAGGGCCCACAUCCCACAAAGACAGGUUCCUCAGAGGCCACGAUAGGACCUGCUGAAGUCGGAAUGGAGGGGGGCUCUGAGCUAGGACAGCCCCUUUUCGGGUCCUCUCCAAGGUCUAGGUGGGGGUGGAGGUGUCUGGAUUUUGGCUCCAUCCUAGGUCAGUGUCUGACCUCACCUCACACACACAAGGCUUGGCUGGCCGGAGAGGGCCACCGGAUGACGUGGUUCCCUGCAGGUCACUAAACACUGAGUCACAGAGGUGGGGUGAGGCCCCACCUGGGGAUCUCAACCUUUGGUCCCCAAUGUUGAUGAAGCCCAGAUGGGAGUCAGGGUCCUCCCACUGACUGUUUCUCCUGUCCCCACCCCUCACAACACCGACUCCCAAGCAAUUGCACAUAAAUCCGUAAACCACCCGUGGGGGCCUGCAGGUGGCAGGCAGAGCCUGGUGUGGGGCCCCUGCCCCCAGUGCUCUGUUCCUUCCUCAGUUCAUUUUCUACACUGUCUGGUUUUGUCCCAGGGAACUAGGAAAGCACAGAAGUAAUUGUAGCCACGCAAUUCCAGAACCACCAACUGCAAGCCGUGGAAUCCUGGGAGCUGCAGACACAGAACUCGCAUCCACAGGACCCCAGAGCCUCAGGCUGCAGAGCGCAGGCCACAGAGCCCUGGAGCCACAGGCUGAUCUGCAGCCGGGAGCAUCCCAGAACCACAGGACCCAGACACACAGCCCAGGCAAUCCGAGCACCAAGGGACUCAAAUCUGCAGCUCACAGAGUCUGCAGAGACCACAGCAGGUUGGGUUAACGGCAUGGAGAACAGUCACCCCCCCCACCACCACCACCAGCAGCCCCCGCCGCAGCCCGGCCCUUCGGGCGAGAGGAGGAACCACCAUUGGAGAAGUUACAAGUUGAUGAUUGACCCGGCUCUGAAAAAGGGGCAUCAUAAACUGUACCGCUACGAUGGGCAGCAUUUCAGCCUGGCGAUGUCCAGCAACCGCCCGGUGGAAAUUGUCGAAGAUCCCCGGGUCGUCGGGAUCUGGACCAAAAACAAGGAGCUGGAGCUGUCGGUGCCCAAAUUCAAGAUCGAUGAGUUCUACGUGGGCCCGGUGCCUCCGAAGCAGGUGACAUUUGCCAAGCUGAAUGAUAACAUCCGUGAAAACUUCCUGAGGGACAUGUGCAAGAAGUAUGGGGAGGUGGAGGAGGUGGAGAUUUUGUACAACCCCAAGACCAAGAAGCACCUGGGCAUCGCCAAGGUGGUCUUUGCCACGGUCCGGGGAGCCAAGGAUGCCGUUCAGCACUUGCACAGCACUUCCGUCAUGGGCAACAUUAUCCACGUGGAGCUGGACACCAAAGGGGAAACCCGAAUGCGGUUCUAUGAACUGUUGGUCACUGGCCGAUACACCCCCCAGACCCUCCCAGUGGGCGAGCUGGACGCUGUCUCUCCAAUCGUGAAUGAGACCCUGCAGCUGUCAGAUGCCCUGAAGCGCCUCAAGGAUGGAGGCCUGUCUGCAGGCUGUGGCUCCGGCUCCUCCUCUGUCACCCCCAAUAGCGGUGGGACACCCUUCUCCCAGGACACAGCUUAUUCCAGCUGCCGCCUGGACACACCCAACUCCUAUGGACAGGGCACCCCGCUCACACCGCGCCUGGGCACCCCUUUCUCACAGGACUCCAGCUACUCCAGCCGCCAGCCCACACCCUCAUACCUCUUCAGCCAGGACCCUGCAGUGACCUUCAAGGCCCGGCGCCACGAGAGCAAGUUCACGGACGCCUACAACCGCCGCCACGAACAUCAUUAUGUACACAAUUCUCCCGCGGUCACUGCGGUGGCCGGGGCCACAGCCGCUUUCCGGGGUUCCUCGGACCUCCCGUUCGGAGCAGUCGGCGGCACUGGGGGCAGCAGCGGUCCCCCGUUCAAGGCUCAACCACAGGAUUCAGCCACAUUUGCCCACACUCCACCACCCGCCCAAGCAACCCCUGCUCCUGGAUUCAAGUCUGCUUUCUCUCCGUAUCAGACCCCAGUGGCCCACUUCCCUCCACCCCCGGAAGAGCCCACCGCCACAGCCGCUUUUGGGGCCCGCGACAGUGGGGAGUUCCGGAGGGCACCGGCGCCCCCACCCCUGCCACCUGCUGAGCCUCUGGCCAAGGAGAAGCCAGGCACGCCACCCGGCCCGCCGCCCCCCGACACCAACAGCAUGGAGCUGGGCGGCCGGCCCACCUUCGGCUGGAGUCCUGAGCCCUGUGACAGCCCUGGCACGCCCACGCUGGAGUCGUCCCCUGCAGGGCCAGAGAAACCCCACGACAGCCUGGACUCGCGCAUCGAGAUGCUGCUGAAGGAGCAGCGCACCAAGCUGCUCUUCCUGAGGGAGCCGGACUCGGACACCGAGCUGCAGAUGGAGGGCAGCCCCAUCUCCUCCUCCUCCUCCCAGCUCUCCCCACUGGCCCCCUUUGGCACCAACUCCCAGCCAGGCUUCCGGGGCCCCACGCCCCCCUCGUCACGCCCCUCCAGCACCGGCCUGGAGGAUAUCAGCCCAACACCCCUCCCAGACUCCGACGAGGACGAGGAGCUCGACCUGGGCCUUGGGCCUCGGCCUCCACCUGAGCCAGGCCCCCCGGACCCUGCUGGGCUUCUGAGCCAGACAGCUGAGGUGGCCUUGGACCUGGUUGGAGACAGAACCCCGACCUCAGAGAAGAUGGAUGAGGGCCAGCAGUCCUCAGGCGAGGACAUGGAGAUCUCGGAUGACGAGAUGCCCUCGGCCCCCAUCACCAGCGCUGACUGCCCCAAGCCCAUGGUGGUGACCCCAGGAGCGGCAGCCGUGGCAGCCCCUUCUGUGCUAGCCCCAACCCUGCCGCUGCCCCCGCCACCUGGCUUCCCCCCGCUGCCCCCCCCACCACCACCACCCCCACCGCAGCCUGGCUUCCCCAUGCCCCCACCGCUGCCCCCACCGCCGCCCCCACCCCCUCCAGCCCACCCUGCUGUGACAGUGCCCCCACCACCCUUGCCAGCGCCGCCUGGAGUCCCGCCCCCACCCAUCCUGCCACCACUGCCCCCCUUUCCGCCGGGCCUGUUCCCUGUGAUGCAGGUGGACAUGAGCCACGUGCUGGGUGGCCAGUGGGGCGGCAUGCCCAUGUCCUUCCAGAUGCAAACGCAGGUGCUCAGCCGGCUGAUGACGGGCCAGGGCGCCUGCCCCUACCCGCCCUUCAUGGCCGCUGCGGCCGCCGCUGCCUCAGCUGGGCUCCAGUUUGUCAACCUGCCGCCCUACCGGGGCCCCUUCUCCCUGAGCAACUCCGGCCCAGGCCGCGGGCAGCACUGGCCACCACUGCCCAAGUUUGACCCGUCAGUGCCUCCACCAGGCUACAUGCCACGCCAGGAGGACCCACACAAAGCCACGGUGGAUGGCGUCCUGCUGGUGGUCCUCAAAGAACUCAAGGCCAUCAUGAAGCGUGACCUGAACCGCAAGAUGGUGGAAGUGGUGGCUUUCCGGGCCUUUGACGAGUGGUGGGACAAGAAGGAGCGGAUGGCCAAGGCCUCGCUGACCCCGGUGAAGUCGGGCGAGCACAAGGACGAGGACAGGCCGAAGCCCAAGGACCGCAUCGCCUCGUGCCUGCUGGAGUCAUGGGGCAAGGGCGAGGGCCUGGGCUACGAGGGCCUGGGCCUGGGCAUUGGGCUGCGUGGGGCCAUUCGCCUGCCCUCCUUCAAGGUCAAGAGGAAGGAGCCACCAGACACCACCUCAUCUGGCGACCAGAAGCGGCUGCGGCCCUCGACCUCUGUGGAUGAGGAAGAUGAAGAGUCCGAGCGAGAGCGAGACCGGGAUAUGGCAGACACCCCCUGUGAGCUCGCCAAGCGGGACCCCAAGGGCGUGGGUGUGCGGCGGCGGCCGGCGCGGCCUCUGGAGCUGGACAGUGGUGGGGAGGAGGACGAGAAGGAGUCAUUGUCGGCGUCCUCGUCCUCAUCCGCGUCAUCAUCCUCGGGGUCCUCAACCACCUCACCCUCGUCCUCGGCCUCCGACAAGGAGGAGGAACAGGAGAGCACCGAGGAGGAAGAGGAGGCGGAGGAGGAGGAGGAGGAGGAAGUCCCCAGGAGCCAGCUCUCCUCCUCCUCAACCUCAUCCACAUCAGAUAAGGAUGACGACGAUGACGACAGUGAUGACCGGGACGAGUCUGAGAACGAUGACGAGGACACAGCCCUGUCAGAGGCGAGUGAGAAGGACGAAGGGGACUCGGAUGAAGAGGAGACAGUGAGCAUUGUAACCUCCAAGGCCGAAGCCACGUCGUCCAGUGAGAGUUCCGAGUCUUCUGAGUUUGAGUCAAGCUCCGAGUCCUCGCCCUCAUCCUCGGAGGAUGAGGAGGAGGUAGUGGCCAGGGAAGAGGAGGAAGAAGAGGAGGAGGAGGAGAUGGUGGCCGAGGAAAGCAUGGCUUCUGCAGGCCCUGAGGACUUUGAGCAGGACGGGGAGGAAGCGGCUCUGGCCCCGGGGGCACCUGCAGUGGACUCGUUGGGCAUGGAAGAGGAGGUGGACAUCGAGACUGAGGCUGUGGCCCCUGAGGAGCGGCCCUCCAUGCUGGACGAGCCCCCCUUGCCUGUGGGUGUUGAAGAGCCAGCGGACUCCAGGGAGCCGCCUGAGGAACCAGGCCUGAGCCAGGAAGGGGCCAUGUUGCUGUCUCCAGAGCCCCCUGCCAAGGAGGUGGAGGCUCGACCCCCAUUGUCCCCUGAGCGAGCUCCAGAACAUGACCUGGAAGUGGAGCCGGAGCCCCCUAUGAUGCUCCCCUUGCCGCUGCAACCACCAUUGCCGCCCCCACGACCACCCCGGCCACCCAGCCCACCGCCGGAGCCUGAGACCACAGAUGCCUCACACCCAUCUGUCCCUCCGGAGCCCCUUGCCGAGGACCACCCCCCGCAUACUCCAGGCCUCUGUGGCAGCCUGGCCAAGUCGCAGAGCACAGAGACGGUGCCAGCCACACCAGGCGGGGAGCCCCCGCUAUCAGGGGGCAGCAGUGGCCUGUCCCUGAGCUCUCCGCAAGUGCCCGGCAGCCCCUUCUCCUACCCAGCCCCGUCCCCUAGCUUGAGCAGUGGGGGCCUCCCUCGGACACCUGGCCGGGACUUCAGCUUCACACCCACCUUCUCCGAGCCCAGCGGGCCCUUGCUCCUGCCCGUCUGCCCACUCCCCACUGGCCGACGCGAUGAACGCUCCGGGCCCCUGGCCUCCCCGGUGCUCCUGGAGACGGGCCUGCCCCUCCCUCUGCCCCUUCCCCUGCCCUUGCCCUUGGCAUUGCCCGCCGUCUUGCGGGCCCAGGCUCGUGCGCCCACCCCGCUGCCACCCCUGCUGCCCGCCCCCCUGGCCUCUUGCCCUCCCCCAAUGAAGAGGAAGCCGGGCCGGCCCCGGCGAUCCCCACCAUCUAUGCUCUCCUUGGAUGGGCCCUUGGUCCGACCACCAGCAGGGGCCGCCCUUGGAAGGGAACUCCUGCUCCUGCCGGGCCAGCCACAGACCCCCGUCUUCCCCAGCACCCAUGACCCCCGGACGGUGACCCUGGACUUCCGGAACGCGGGGAUCCCAGCCCCUCCACCACCCCUUCCCCCCCAGCCACCCCCACCCCCACCUCCCCCACCUGUAGAGCCCACCAAGCUGCCCUUUAAGGAGCUAGACAACCAGUGGCCCUCCGAGGCCAUUCCUCCGGGCCCCCGUGGGCGCGAUGAGGUCACUGAGGAAUACAUGGAGUUGGCCAAGAGCCGGGGGCCGUGGCGCCGGCCACCUAAGAAGCGCCAUGAGGACCUGGUGCCACCUGCGGGCUCGCCCGAACUCUCGCCACCCCAGCCCCUCUUCCGGCCCCGCUCGGAGUUUGAGGAGAUGACCAUCCUGUAUGACAUCUGGAACGGUGGCAUCGAUGAGGAGGACAUCCGCUUCCUGUGUGUCACCUACGAGCGACUGCUACAGCAGGACAAUGGCAUGGACUGGCUUAACGACACGCUCUGGGUCUACCAUCCCUCCACCAGCCUCUCUUCAGCUAAGAAGAAGAAACGGGACGAUGGCAUCCGCGAGCACGUGACGGGCUGUGCCCGCAGUGAGGGCUUCUACACCAUCGACAAGAAGGACAAGCUCAGAUACCUCAACAGCAGCCGUGCCAGCACCGAUGAGCCCCCCGCAGACACCCAGGGCAUGAGCAUCCCAGCACAGCCCCACGCCUCCACCCGGGCAGGCUCGGAGCGGCGUUCGGAGCAGCGCCGCCUGCUGUCCUCCUUCACUGGCAGCUGUGACAGUGACCUGCUCAAGUUCAACCAGCUCAAGUUCCGGAAGAAAAAGCUCAAGUUCUGCAAGAGCCACAUUCACGACUGGGGCUUGUUCGCCAUGGAGCCCAUCGCGGCUGACGAGAUGGUCAUCGAGUACGUGGGCCAGAAUAUCCGUCAGGUGAUCGCAGACAUGCGGGAGAAGCGUUAUGAGGACGAGGGCAUCGGGAGCAGCUACAUGUUCCGGGUGGACCAUGACACCAUCAUCGACGCCACCAAGUGCGGCAACUUCGCGCGCUUCAUCAACCACAGCUGCAACCCCAACUGCUAUGCCAAGGUGAUCACGGUGGAGUCACAGAAGAAGAUAGUCAUCUACUCGAAGCAGCACAUUAACGUCAAUGAGGAGAUUACCUAUGACUAUAAGUUCCCCAUCGAGGACGUCAAGAUCCCCUGCCUCUGUGGCUCCGAGAACUGCCGGGGGACCCUCAACUAGGCCCCGGCACCAGACUCAAAGGAUGUCAGCCGUAGCCCUGGGACUCCCGAGCGUGGAGCCCCUGGCCCCGGGGCCCGGCCCCCCGCGCCCGCCCCCAUUUCAGGUGCUGUCCUCUACCCAGCGGCCAUUCAGGGCCUGGCGCCCCACACUACCCCCUGGAGCCCCUGGCUCCGGCCCCUCCGCGGGAAAGGGCUUCUCUGUCGUUCAGCCCACGUCUCUCUCAUUUUAACAAACGCCCCUUUCAGGAUUUCUGUUUAACUCCAGCAUCAGCUUCUCUCUCUCCGUCUCUCCUCCCCUCUCUCUCUUCUCUGUCUCUUCUCUCUCCCACCAUCACCCUCGGCCUCUUCCUGUGAAUGCUGCUACGUUGUUUUGUCUUCUCUAUUUUUUUCCUCGUUGUGAGAAAAGACAUUUAACCGUUGAAAUGUGAAGGUGGAAUCAGAGAGGGGCCCCGCGGGGGUCUGCAGAGGCCUCAGUGUGGCUGUGCGUGGCCCGUGUCCUGGAAGCCACCCGGACCUGGACGCAGGGCCAGGUGCUGUGGGAAGGAUGGAGGCCCCCACGGCCUUGACCUCAGAACACUACGCCCUGAAAGCGCCCCUCACUGCCCGUGGGCACAGUGAGGAGACCCCACACCUUUCCCCACCCGAGCUGCAGCCUGUUCCUUCCCCAGAGGCCUGGGGCACCACUGACCCGGUGGACCCUGAUGGAGCUAAGCUGUCCCAGGCAGGGGUCUCCGCUCUGGGCUUUCCCUGCCACCUCACACCCCAGCACCCCCUAAACCUUGGGUUCAAUGUUUACUUUCUCAUUCGGAUGCCAGCAACGCGGGAGCCUCUCGGAGGCCCCAGUGCAGGUGAGGGGCGCUGAGAACGCGGGCAGCCACUCUCUUCUGCCCUUGCCUUCGCCCUGGGUGGGACAGGGCUCCCAAGGGCAGGCGGGUCCCCCAGUCCCGCCAUUACGGGUUGUCAGACCGUCUGCGUGUGGCAUUUUUUGGCUUAUAAGCUUCACCCACUCACCCCCAACCCACACCCCACAUCCCCCUGCCGGCAGCCCCUCAACCUAAGAAGGCCAGAGCAUAUUUAUUUUCGGAGGGAGCAGAUUACUUCUCCCAGAGAAAGGAAAAUCUUGGAAAAGAUUUAAAAACACAAAUCUAAGCCUUGACGGUUUUUUUUUCCCUUUUGACCCCCUUCCCAUCUCUUCAGAAUUUAUUCCCAUGGCUUUUUUUUUUCUUGUGCGUGUAUAAAAUCAAAAGGAAGGGGAAAAAGGUUUUUGAAGUUCAGAACCAACUUCUGUAUAUAGAGGCUGCCGCAAAGGACUUUCUCUUGGGAACAUUGUUUCUUGUAGAAACAUGCGGGAAGACAUUUUUUGCUCAUUUCUUUGUACUUCCAAAAAAAAAGGAAAAAAAAGACAAAAGCAAGUCCCCCCGUACCCCAGAAAGCAGAGGAGGCGUGUAAAUAAUUUCUGGAAAGUGACUGUUGUGACCCGGAGUCCUCAUCAAGAUGAGCGCGCUCCAUGAGGGAGCUGCUCCCACCCUGCGGACGCAGGCGGCCGGAGCCUCUGGUAUCUCAGCUUGUGUCAAGCUUGUUAUCAUGUAAAUUCUGUACAAAGAAUUGUUAUUUUUCUCUUUUUUGUUGUUGGUGGUUUUGUUGUGUGUUUUUUGUUGUUUUUUUUUUAUUCCUUUCCCCCAGGCCCUCUCUAUUUGAGACUGUGCCCGCCGGUUUCAAGAUCAAGGAAAUUGGUGGCAACAAGACACAGAUGGGGUACCUGGGCACAGCGGCGAACUUCUCUUCCGUUUGCGGUUUUCUGCCUAAUUGUGCAACUGAGGAAAUAAUUUAUUUUUCACAUGAGGAAAUGCGUAGCUUGUAGAGACGGCUGAUUCAAGUUACAUGUACAGCCUCCAAAGGGCUGUCUCCAUUCUGUCCCCUUCCCAUAAAAGAAGUGGGGGUGUUCGAGAAGACCAGGGAAGGGACCCUUGCCUCACCCCUCCCCCUGGCCUCACCUUGCUCCCAGCCAUCGUGCCCAGUGUUAACCUCGGCUGGCCUUCACUAAGGGGACUAGACCUCCCUCUCCCCAGGAGCCCCAGCCCCAGAGUGGUUUGCAAUAAUCAAGAUAUGUGUCGAGUCAUUUUUCUUUCAACUCCCUCAUUUUUCAUUGAACAAAUCUCUGCUUUUCAAGAGUUGGGGGUUUCUGCUAUUUUUUGCUUUCUCUCCCUCCCCCUGCAAAGAUGAGAACCAAUGAGUUUUAGGGAUGUUUGUGCGGGUAGACUCCAUCAUCCAUAUGUAACUUGUUUUGAAGAGAAGUGUUUCCGUUGUGUGUCUUGAUGUAAAUAUUUGUUCAUAUUUUUGUGAAUUCAAUACUAUGUACCAUUGUAUUAUAGUAACUUUUAUAAAGCAAACCAUAAAUAUACUGACUUUUCUUACAGA